AUCAGUCGCGCAGCUGUGUUCGCGGACUCAGGUGGAAGGAAUUUCUUCUCUUCGUUGACGUUGCUGGUGUUCACUGUUUGGAAUUAGUCAAGUUUCGGGAAUCACCGUCGCUGCCAUCAACAUGUCGGUCCCAAGCGCUCUCAUGAAGCAACCGCCCAUUCAGUCUACGGCUGGGGCCGUCCCAGUUCGCAAUGAGAAAGGUGAGAUUUCAAUGGAAAAAGUGAAGGUAAAGCGUUAUGUGUCCGGAAAAAGGCCAGACUAUGCCCCUAUGGAGUCCUCAGAUGAGGAGGAUGAAGAAUUUCAGUUCAUUAAGAAAGCCAAAGAACAAGAAGCAGAGCCUGAGGAACAGGAGGAGGAUUCAUCCAGUGACCCCCGGCUACGGCGUUUACAGAACCGUAUUAGUGAAGAUGUGGAAGAGAGAUUGGCUCGACAUCGAAAAAUAGUGGAACCUGAAGUGGUAGGAGAGAGUGACUCAGAAGUAGAAGGAGAUGCUUGGCGCAUGGAACGAGAAGACAGCAGUGAAGAAGAGGAGGAGGAAAUUGAUGAUGAGGAAAUAGAGCGGCGGCGUGGCAUGAUGCGUCAGCGAGCACAGGAGAGAAAAAAUGAAGAGAUGGAAGUCAUGGAAGUGGAAGAUGAGGGUCGUUCUGGAGAGGAGUCAGAAUCAGAGUCUGAGUAUGAAGAGUACACAGACAGUGAAGAUGAGAUGGAGCCUCGCCUUAAGCCAGUCUUCAUUCGAAAGAAGGACCGAGUGACAGUUCAAGAACGUGAAGCCGAAGCAUUGAAACAGAAGGAGCUGGAGCAGGAAGCAAAACGCAUGGCUGAGGAAAGGCGCAAGUACACACUCAAGAUUGUCGAAGAGGAAACCAAAAAAGAGCUGGAAGAGAACAAGCGAUCCCUGGCUGCAUUGGAUGCACUCAAUACUGAUGAUGAAAAUGAUGAGGAGGAAUAUGAGGCAUGGAAAGUUCGAGAGCUAAAAAGAAUCAAGAGGGACAGAGAAGAUCGAGAAGCGCUUGAGAAGGAGAAAGCAGAAAUUGAACGCAUGCGAAACCUGACUGAGGAAGAGAGGAGAGCUGAACUUCGGGCAAACGGCAAAGUCAUUACCAACAAAGCUGUUAAGGGCAAAUACAAGUUCUUACAGAAGUAUUAUCACCGGGGUGCCUUCUUCAUGGAUGAGGAUGAAGAAGUAUACAAGAGAGAUUUCAGCGCUCCUACCCUGGAGGAUCAUUUCAAUAAAACCAUUCUUCCUAAAGUCAUGCAGGUCAAGAACUUUGGACGCUCAGGUCGCACCAAAUACACUCACCUUGUGGAUCAAGAUACCACCUCCUUUGACUCAGCUUGGGGCCAAGAGAGUGCCCAGAACACAAAGUUCUUCAAACAAAAGGCAGCUGGGGUACGAGAUGUAUUUGAGCGGCCAUCUGCCAAGAAGCGGAAAACUACCUAGGGUCCAACUGCUUAUUCUUCCAACUGUGGAACACAAGGGGAGUCUCAGCAUCUGGUCCUUGAUUUGGUUUUUUCAUUGUUUCCUUGGCCCCUGUAUCCAGAUAUUGGACUUACUGCUAUACUUGUGAUACUGGGUAGCCCAGACUUUGAAGGUGCUUUGUGAGGUUUGGACUCAUGCUGAGAAACCCACAGGAAAGCACUGUCCAGGUAGGAUUAGAGGCUUCCCACUUAAAACUAUUUCUGAGAAAUCUUAGGUUUUAUCACUGCUAUGGUUUCCCAUAUUUACUUGGGACUGUUCUGACUUUCUUUUUCCAGCCCUUAGCUUGGGUUAGAAAAGUGGACAUGUAAGUGAACAAUGCAUUACUUCUACCUUAGGUUUAGGAGUAAUAUACCCGGAAAUCUAAGCUCAUGGAAACAUGUUUUCCAUUUUUGCUUGGAGUCCGUUUUUCUAGUUGUACAUACUUUUUGAUCCAUAUAUGUGUGCAUGUCAAGAAAUAAAAGAAUCACACAACAAGGAGAUUUUUAGCAUGAUACUGGAAAUAAAAUGUCCAAGCUGACAAGUAUUAAUUGCCUAUUAAAGUAAAAGAUAACAAUUGUCAGGCA